AUGCUUUCCUUCACUGUCCAGUUUGCAGAGCCGUCUUGGAGCUGGCGCGGGUCCUCCCUCUGUCGAACUGGCGCGCCCUCGUCCGCCCACAAGUCCUUGGAAAGCGCAGGCCUCGUGCGCUCUCCAGCGCCCUUCCAGGGCGCAAGGGCAGGACAGGUACAUCCCGCGUGCUGCGGUGGCGAUCAGCGCGGACACGGAACCUGGCUCCACCCGUCCGCCCAGCCUUGGGGUUCUGCCAGAGCGCCGGGCGCAGAGCAAGCGGGUCUGAGCUCCAGCACCUUUGGCAGCUCCCGGCCCCGGGGUGCGAACGGCGGCCGUGGCUCACCGCUUCAGGAGCAGGCGACCAGGACACUAGGAAGAGAAGCCCGGACCAGGGCUAGUUUGUUUCCCCAACUCCUCUGGCCAGCUCAGGUUCUUAAACCCGCCGUGCAACAGACGCAGGGGAAGAUGAGCAGGUGCGAGACAGGGAGAAGCCAUCCUACUUCUGGCUCCAGCGGCAGCGGUACCAGUGGCUGUAUACAACAGGGGGCCCGAGAACCAUCUGAGGCUCCAGCGGAGACACAGGAUUGGCUUCCGCUCCCCAGCAGUGGGGACGUCUCCAGACAUUCAGCAGCUCCAGCCCGGGGACUGCUGCAGCUUCUACCCUCUGGCUUACCACGUUUUAUCUCCAGCUCUUGCAUAAUUCAAAGCACAAUACUUCUGUGGGGUGAAUGAGUAUCUUCAACUGAUAUAGCAGCAGGACUUGGAGGGGAAAGUGGAACUUCCUCAAGUUUUGAUCAAGAGAAAGUAAGCAGCUGGGUGUGGUAGCUUGUGCCUGCAAUCCCAAAACUUUGGGAGGCCAAGGUGGGAGAUC